ACUAGGGGAUGAGCCCGAACUAGGGAUGUGACAGAGCGCGAGACCCAGCCUAAAGAGAGCCCGGAGCCAGCGUGGGAGGCCGCUGCCGUCGCGCGCCUUGGUUUUUCUGUUCCUUUUUUUUUUUUUUUUUUAACUUCCUGCCUAUACACACGCAGCCAUCAGCCCACAAAGACAUGACUACCAACGCGGGCCCCUUGCACCCAUACUGGCCUCAGCACCUAAGACUGGACAACUUUGUACCUAAUGACCGCCCCACCUGGCAUAUACUGGCUGGCCUCUUCUCUGUCACAGGGGUCUUAGUCGUGACCACAUGGCUGUUGUCAGGUCGUGCUGCGGUUGUCCCAUUGGGGACUUGGCGGCGACUGUCCCUGUGCUGGUUUGCAGUGUGUGGGUUCAUUCACCUGGUGAUCGAGGGCUGGUUCGUUCUCUACUACGAAGACCUGCUUGGAGACCAAGCCUUCUUAUCUCAACUCUGGAAAGAGUAUGCCAAGGGAGACAGCCGAUACAUCCUGGGUGACAACUUCACAGUGUGCAUGGAAACCAUCACAGCUUGCCUGUGGGGACCACUCAGCCUGUGGGUGGUGAUCGCCUUUCUCCGCCAGCAUCCCCUCCGCUUCAUUCUACAGCUUGUGGUCUCUGUGGGCCAGAUCUAUGGGGAUGUGCUCUACUUCCUGACAGAGCACCGCGACGGAUUCCAGCACGGAGAGCUGGGCCACCCUCUCUACUUCUGGUUUUACUUUGUCUUCAUGAAUGCCCUGUGGCUGGUGCUGCCUGGAGUCCUUGUGCUUGAUGCUGUGAAGCACCUCACUCAUGCCCAGAGCACGCUGGAUGCCAAGGCCACAAAAGCCAAGAGCAAGAAGAACUGAGGAGUGGUGGACCAGGCUCGAACACUGGCCGAGGAGGAGCUCUCUGCCUGCCAGAAGAGUCUAGUCCUGCUCCCACAGUUUGGAGGGACAAAGCUAAUUGAUCUGUCACACUCAGGCUCAUGGGCAGGCACAAGAAGGGGAAUAAAGGGGCUGUGUGAAGGCACUGCUGGGAGCCAUUAGAACACAGAUACAAGAGAAGCCAGGAGGUCUAUGAUGGUGACGAUUUUUAAAAUCAGGAAAUAAAAGAUCUUGACUCUAA